GCAGCAGCCGGGGCGGCGGCGAGGACGGCGGCCACGGAAGCGGCCAAGGGGGCGGUGGCGCAGAGAGGGGUGCGGAGCGGGCGGAAGAGGCGUCUGUGUCGCAGCUUGGUCUCAGAGGAGCAUCGCUGGGCUCGUCUCAAUUUGGCCCUGCUGUAUUUCAAGUGCUCGGUAGCCACAUGUGGCAAGUGGCCAUCACUGUGGCCAUUGCAGCUCCAAAGGGACAGGAGAGUUGAUGGAAAUUAGACACUGCAUUCUACAGCCUCAUGAGCCCAAGAGAGCAAACCUUGGUUUGCUGAAAAUCAGCAGAUAAGGCAAUUGAAAGGGAAGAAGGGCUUUCAAAUGGAGGCUGCAGUUGAGGGAGAAGGAUUUACCUUGGCAGUUAAGGGAUUAUCCUGCUAGUUCUCUGAUGUUCCUACUGUAGAGAACCAGGAUUUUGCUCACUUACCUGGAACAACGACUAUCGUCUAUUCCACAAGAUGAGUAACAGCCACCCUCUUCGCCCCUUUACUGCAGUGGGGGAAAUUGAUCAUGUGCACAUUUUGUCUGAACAUAUUGGUGCCUUGUUGAUUGGGGAAGAAUAUGGCGACGUCACAUUCGUGGUGGAAAAGAAACGUUUUCCUGCCCACAGGGUAAUUUUAGCAGCCAGGUGCCAAUAUUUUCGAGCAUUAUUAUAUGGUGGAAUGCGAGAGUCUCAGCCUGAAGCAGAAAUUCCUCUCCAAGACACCACUGCAGAAGCAUUCACAAUGCUACUCAAAUAUAUCUACACUGGGCGGGCAACGCUGACAGAUGAGAAGGAGGAGGUGCUGCUGGACUUUUUGAGCCUGGCUCAUAAAUAUGGAUUUCCAGAGCUAGAGGAUUCUACCUCUGAGUAUCUCUGCACCAUACUUAACAUUCAGAAUGUCUGCAUGACUUUUGAUGUUGCCAGUCUCUACUCACUUCCCAAGUUAACUUGUAUGUGCUGCAUGUUUAUGGAUAGGAAUGCUCAGGAAGUCCUCUCAAGUGAAGGUUUCCUCUCCCUUUCUAAGACAGCACUUUUAAACAUCGUGUUAAGAGACUCAUUUGCAGCUCCCGAAAAAGAUAUUUUCCUAGCCUUAUUAAACUGGUGUAAGCACAAUUCAAAGGAGAAUCAUGCUGAAAUCAUGCAGGCUGUGCGUUUACCUCUCAUGAGCCUCACAGAGCUUCUGAAUGUUGUGAGGCCUUCAGGACUGCUGUCUCCUGAUGCCAUCCUGGAUGCCAUUAAAGUGCGAUCUGAGAGCCGGGAUAUGGACCUCAAUUAUAGAGGCAUGCUCAUACCAGAAGAAAACAUUGCAACUAUGAAGUAUGGAGCCCAAGUUGUAAAGGGGGAGCUGAAAUCAGCCUUAUUAGAUGGUGAUACUCAAAAUUAUGAUUUGGAUCAUGGAUUUUCAAGGCACCCAAUUGAUGAUGACUGCCGUUCCGGCAUCGAGAUUAAGCUAGGUCAGCCAUCCAUUAUCAAUCACAUACGGAUACUCUUGUGGGACCGAGAUAGCCGGUCUUACUCAUACUUCAUUGAAGUGUCAAUGGAUGAACUUGAUUGGGUCAGAGUGAUAGAUCAUUCACAAUAUCUGUGUCGUUCUUGGCAGAAAUUAUAUUUUCCAGCCCGUGUCUGCAGGUAUAUUCGAAUUGUUGGGACUCACAACACAGUGAACAAGAUUUUUCACAUUGUGGCUUUUGAAUGUAUGUUUACAAACAAAACCUUCACUCUUGAGAAGGGGCUGAUAGUUCCCAUGGAGAAUGUUGCAACAAUUGCUGAUUGUGCCAGUGUGAUUGAAGGAGUCAGUCGGAGCCGAAAUGCCUUGCUGAAUGGGGACACUAAGAAUUAUGACUGGGAUUCUGGCUACACAUGUCACCAGCUAGGAAGUGGUGCGAUUGUGGUUCAGUUGGCACAACCGUACAUGAUUGGGUCAAUACGGUUACUACUUUGGGAUUGUGAUGAUCGAAGCUAUAGCUACUACGUUGAGGUUUCUACCAACCAGCAACAGUGGACCAUGGUUGCUGACAGAACUAAAGUCUCCUGCAAGUCCUGGCAGUCAGUAACUUUUGAAAGGCAGCCUGCCUCCUUCAUCCGUAUCGUUGGGACACACAACACAGCAAAUGAGGUGUUCCACUGUGUCCACUUUGAGUGUCCAGAGCAGCAGAGCAGCCAGAAGGAGGAAAAUAGUGAGGAAUCGGGGACAGGGGACACCAGCCUGGCCGGUCAGCAGCUCGACUCCCAUGCGCUGCGGGCGCCUAGUGGCAGCUCACUACCCUCCAGCCCAGGCUCCAACUCACGCUCCCCCAACCGGCAGCACCAAUAAAGGAGGCAGCGGGCCUGGUGUGACUUGGUGGGCUCGGGCAACGGCAGGAAACGGUCUCCUCCCUGAGCAGGGGUCUCUGUUGACUGCCCCCACCUCUGCCCCUUUCCAGGGAGGAGCCGACCUAGCUGCAAAAGCAGACACCGAACAGGUUUUCUCCCAAGGACAGAAAGGGGCUGCUUUGUUCUUCUCAAUUUAUCCAAAUCAGGCAGGUCUCAAGGGGGAGAAAAUGGGUCUUCAAUCUUCAUCAAGUCCACCAUUAACACCCUACCUCUCUAAUCUAGCCCAGGCGCAGGGAACAGGAGGAAGUCAUAGACAGGCCUGUGUUGGAAUACAAAAAUGGCACGCAAACACUCAGGCGGAGGAGAAAGCCAUUGGGCCUUUGCUACCUGGAGGCACCCUUUAGGAAUGGGCCUCCAUAGAGUGUUCAUUCUGCUGGAAUACAUUGCCCUGGCAACUAAAUGAUUUUUUAUUUGUUUUAGUUAUUCUCCACUCAGUGAAUCAUAGGUGUUCCGGAUCUAUUUGAAAUGCUCAAACAGCAAAUCACUAGUUUUAAUCCCUUUUGAUGCUAUAAUUUUCCUUCCUUGGUUUUGAACGGUUCAGCUUGCGGGGACAGAGACCCAUCGUGCAUGUCUCCUAAAUGAGACACGGAUGCAGCUCAUCCUGGCACUUGGGCCACAGAGGAAGUGCCACAAAUGCACACAAGCAAAUCAACCUGUGGACACUGGAGUUAAUAGUCACUCGUGUGGCUGAGUUACUCACCUGUCAUUCCUGACAUGGAUCCAGCCUUUAAGCUUGGGAGGCUGACAAGGAAAUAGUUACUAUGCCCGCUGCUAAUUCACUGUUCCGAAGUCCAUGUAGAUAAACAUAUACCGAGUUCUGGCGUGGCCAAACCUGCCGGGGACUGCCGUGGCUUAGCUGCCCCUCCAGUUGUGUUUAUCGAAGCAUUGGAGAGGCAGCCACCUGCCCAUCAGCGUCAGGAACGCAGAACUGGGACUCCGUGCUUCCCCCACACCACAGUACUCAACUGGGGACUGAAAAAUAGCAGUUCCAAGAAGCUUUUCUCCUAAUCCUCAUCAAAAGGACCUCAUUUGACGAUGGUGGCUUGAUGUGGCUCCGUCUCCUACUUAGUGAUUUCCAUUCCAGUGCUGCCUGCCCUGGGUAACUGCGCACAACAUUGCCUGCCCCUCCGCUGUCCCCAGAGCUCCGGCCUCUGUCGCCAUCAGCAUCAGCCUGGGAGUCUCCCCAGGACGGCAUGGCACGUGAGCAGCACUGCAGUCCUUGGGUCUUCGGCGCCAACCUGCAACCCUGAUCAAAGGAGGGUGAGGGCGUGGGAGUUUCCUUUCAGGUGUGUCAAAGACAUAUCAGCUGCGCUCUAGAAAGAGCCAACGGGUCAGCCGCUUCCUCCUAGUUUAACUUGAUUUUGAGUGAUUUGUCCAUAUGGAAAUAGUAGGGUAGCAUCAAACUGCGUGAUUAAAUUGGAAGACUGUCUUUCCGUGUGAACACAGGAUGGCAGACAUCAGAGGGCUACCGGGGCAGGGUGGACACGUUCCUGAGGAGAAGCCAGGGUCUGCAGCUCUCCAUCCUCCCCGGUAGCUCCAGCUGCAGGGCUGAGCUGCUUCCUAUCCCCUCAGCUCUGAUCUCUGCCACUUCCCUGUUGUGUGGGAGAGUGGAACACUCCUGGGAUGCCAGGCAUUUCAUAAUGGGAGGAGGCUCCUGUAAGGAACGGUGGGCGCCCGCUCACAGUGGGGGGCCCUCCAGCAUGGUUGCUGACUCUGUCAGCCCCCAGCCCCGGGUUGCCAAUUAGCCAGAGAGCUCCUGCACACACAGCACUUCCUUCCCCAGUGUGUUUUCUACCCAGAUGGGGACAAAGGAGCCAGACAGUCAUAUCAAGGGCAGAGUUCAAACAUUUUGAAAUGAGCCAUUCACAUGCUUCUUUUUAAACAUGGGCAUCACCUGCCCAGAGGCCCUUGGCCUGAAGCAGCAUGCUGCUGACCUUGGGAAGAGAGGGUGGGCUGGUGGGGGUGCUGGAGGAGCUGCCCGGCCCUGCAUCUGCAACCCUCCAGUCCCCUGCCCACAGAGCACGCAGAGCCCUCCUGUGCUCCGGGAACGAGAUAGCAGCUUGGCAGCUCGGCCUCGCAUCUGAAAAGGAAUACGCUGCAAAGCCUCGGCCCUAGACCCACAUCUGCAGCUCCCUGGCCUGUGGCGGUUCUUUCCUUCGGGGCAUGCCCUUCCAGAUCUCUGUCCCUCCUGUCUUCUAGCACUUUAAAGAUGCCCCUUAUCAUCAGAUAAAGAGAAGUAUGGGGACGAUGGGGUGGCACUAACAGUAGAUGUCAUUGGUGAGGACUGAUGGCAAAGUCUCAUUCCCUCACAGCCGCGCUGCCAGCUCGCCUCCCCCUCGCUUUGCUGGGAGCCUGCCCUGGACUCCAAAAGGACACGGGUUCACCUCCUUUCCCAGGCUGGAGGGGUACUGCCCUUCCCUGAGGGGCCUUCUGACUGGGGCAGGAACUCUUUUCGUGUGUCCAGCUGGGCCUGGAGGCCAAGUCAAGGUGUGUCACACCACACACCAGGGCAAGGACCUCAUCUCCAGGGAACAGGGACAAGUGAGUGGCUACCAGAAAGUCCCCGGGCAGCCUGGAGUUCCCCAGAGCCUGGCUGGUCCUACAGAGCACUUCUCCCCUGGGCCACCAGGACCAAAGCGACCUAAACACUUGAAGCUAAAAGCAAGUGCUGAUGAUGGGAUGGGCUGGCACGUGGCUGGGAGGGCUCCUGGGCACCACAGAGCCCUCAGCCCAGCAGAGAGUGGAGGCUCAGUCCGUGGGGAGCGGGGGUUGUGAAGGAGACAUGGCCAAGCCCCUGGUCGGGGAGAUAAGCUCCCCCAUGCCCAGGCCAGCCCCAGGGGCAACAAGCCAACAUGGAGAGAGGUGGCAGGUGAGGCUGACAGGUGGGUGCCUGUGGCCUGGGCCCAUGAGGGCAAUGGUCCUCAGUAACCAAUGGAAAGGACACAAGGGCGCCAUGGUCACCACCACCCAGGCAAAGAAAUGGGAGGUGGCCAGCACCCCCACCCUUCACUUUUCAUUAUUAUUAUUAUUAUUAUUAUUAUUAUUUUUUUUUUUUUUUUUUUUUUUUUUUUUUUUUUUUGAGAGUAGAAAGGCAACUUCAUUGGAGCUUUUGGGGAAAAAAGCCUUCAAAGUCACCUUCUGGCAGCUCUGGGGAGGGUCAUUUGGGGUGGACUGAGAGUGUAGGGCAGGUAGGGUGUGUGCUGGGCAGCAGCUGUGUCCAUGCAGCCAGCACCCAGCAGGGCAGUCUCACAGGAGCCGUUGUGAGCACUUUGGACUUGAAGCAGCUAUGAACCACCCCCCGCCCCCACCGUCUCUCCCUCUCACACACACACACACACACACACACACACACACACACACACACACACACCCGUUUUACCAUUUUCUCAGUGCUUUUUCUGCUUUCAUUCCUUUGAUUUUAGUUAGAAGCACAAGCCAUGAUGGAUGUGGGACUCUUCUCAAUUGCUCUUUAAAUUGUCACUUUUUAAAUCCUAUUAAAUGAAGUGUCGAUUCCUGACAAAUACAUUAAAAGUGUUUUAUUCCUAGAAGAGUUGGGAAAAGAAAUUAUUUUCAGCAAGAGUAGGAUGUUUGUUAAACUGAUUCCUUGGCAAAAAAGAGAAAAAAAGCUUUUGAAUUGUGCAAAAAAUUGCCCAGUAUUAUGCUGUCGCCCCAGUUGUCAAACUGCUGUGCAGAUGGCUCCAGCCCAGUCAACUUCACCUUCUUUUUAAUUUAGAAGAUAACAAAAUUGUAAUCACUUAUCCUUUCCAGAGCCAAGGGGGAAAAGGAAGGUAUAAUCUACAAUAAAAAGCGAGCGUUCUGUGUACUGAGGCCACUUGGUGAUAAAGAGAUGGAGCGCUCCCCUCACAGACUUCAAUUAAGAACCUCCCUUUGGACAGGGAAGAAAGGUGUCAAAGAGGAAAAGAAAAUUAAAUUUGCUUCCUUCCAGGAGUUUUUCCUCAUUAGUGCUUGCUUGUCGGUGUUAUUAUUUUAAUCUUACCUUCUAUGUGGUGACCAGCUCCUCCGAGCGAUGCCCAGGUCGGGCACGGCCCGGGCAGGGCAGGUCUGCAGCGAUGCCGUGGCAGAGGUGGGCAUACUCCAUUUGUUUUGGCAGCUGCAGCCAUUGAUUCUGCAUAUUUUUCCUGACAACAGCCCCGGCAGGAGUUCAGUUAGGAAUUUAAAGUGCAGUUCAUGGUUCUGUGCCACCGUGGCUUUUAUUAUUAUAAUAUUAAAUUAGAAGUUGUCCUAGUGCCUGGUGUUUGCUCAGAGUUUCCAGAAGAGAGGGAAGGGCAAGGUUUAAAUGGCAUGCAGGACAACUGGAAUGCCCCCAUCUCUCUCGCUGACACGGAUCCAGUCAUACCUGGGGCUGGACGGGAUUUGGAGGCCCUGGUCAUUUGCAGAGUGAAUGGUGAAGGGCGCGGAAAAGGUUUGCUUGGAGGAAAGACCGGUUGCAGAGGCGAGGCGGAGGGAGGAGGGGCGGAGGCAGCAGGUCUUUGUUUGUGGUAGGUCUCUGGCUUCCAUCAGGGAGGAGGAAAGAGGCUGUGCCCUUCCUGGCUCUUGGCUGCACCACUGAGGACGCUCCGAGGGACAGCGUGCUCACCCAUCCUUUGCACAGUGCUGGCCCCAAGCCCCACGGCCUUCCAGCUAGGAUUUUCUGCUGGGCUCAUGCAGAGGCAGGGGACAGGUGCAUGGAAGAGCCGCCCCACCCGACACACCAUUGUUUGAAAAUCACUGUUCUCUUUACUCACUUAAAAAAGUGUACAGGGAACACCUGUUCCUGGCAUAAUGCUCCAACCUCGCGGAAGGGGCCAGGUGCCCUUCAUCUGGCUCUGGCUGCUUCCGACCUGGGCCCACGUCAUCGUUCACGUCCUCUGUGACCACCACUGGUCACGGUGCUCCCUGGCCCAGCCUCCAACCCACCCAGCACCCUGGCAUCUCCCAGGCCAGUCUGCUGCACCCAGCGAGCUUCCAGUCAGAAGCCAGGCUGAACGGCCCUCCUGCCCCAUCAGCUUCGUGUCUUCUUUUUUUUAAAGAACUGAAAUAGUCCCCAAGAGGCCUCAUGGCCUGAAGACUCACAAUCAUCCACCUGUAAUUUAUGAUAAAUGUCUGGGAGCAUUUACCAUUUGCGUCCGUGAGUAUUUAUAGCCCUGAAUGGGCGGGGGGGAGGGGGGGUGGAGGAGGCCCUGCAGCCAGGAGCUACACACCUGUCCCCACUAGUGUCCCCUGGUUGACAGAGCCCCCUCAGCCUCCCCAAGGCUGUCACUGCGGCUGUGACAGCUGAGGAGUGCCGCCUUUGAAAGCCAGUGGACAGUCGCUCCACUAGGGGGAGAGGCCCUGGCCCUGGCGCAGAGGAGGCGUUGCGAGGCGGGACGGGGGCUGGAGGGGCUGAGCAGCCUUCAGGGCAGGGACUGGGCCCUGGGUCACUGGAGACGUUGAUAUUAGUCCGUCUGCUGCCAAAUUGCUCCCCACCACAUGAGCCCCAGGGGUUUAUGUCCCAGGAAGGCGAGGGUGCCCAUCUGAGCGGAAUUGGGAGGGGACGGCACCAGCUCAUCUCCCUCAGGGCCUUUGCCUCCUGGUGCUGCCCUGGUGGCUGCUCCUGCACCACAGCCCCUGAUGGCUGCUGCUAGUCCUGAGUUGCUGGGUUUACCCCCAGCCCACACUUCCCACCUGGGCCUGAGGGUGCGGCCAGUGCCCUAGUCCUAGCCACUACAGGAGUCAUUCUGAGACCUGCUGGAGGCCAUGGGGUCUUCCCAGGCCCCUCAAUCAGCUGCUUCCAGGGUCAGCAGGGCAGGGUGCUGCCAGUAAGGUCCUCAGGGAGCACAGCCCGGCCGCCCAGGCUGGGGGAUACUGGGGCAGAGCUUCCAGGUCUGUGGGGCCUGAUCUCUCCCCAAGGCUCUCCAGGCCUUGGUGCGCCCUCCACAGUGACCUUCAGAGAGGCUGCACCCCCUCAGAAGAACAGUGAGAAAUCUCUCCAUCACACGCUCCCUGGUCCUUAUGUCCCUGAGGCCACCCUUCCCCACCCCCCAGUGCCUGGAGAAGCGUGAGACUCUGGAGGGGCGCCAGGAGGCCAGGGGUCCUCAGGGCUAGGCCUGGAGCUCGGCCCAAGAGCUGCUUUUGCGAAGCCUGUCUUGAAUCCGGAUUCACCAGAGAACAAGAGCCUCCCAGCCUUUGGCGUUUCUGGGCCUGUAAAGAUGUGUGUACCUCCCAGGCCACUCUGAUGCAAGGGCAGGGACCAUGCCAGGCCUGGGUUGGGAAUGGCUCUGUGACUCCAGAAGCUCCGUCUAAAACUCCAAAGAUGCCCAAAAGGCUGUGCUGCUAUGUGGAAUGUGUAUUAUUUGUGAGCACGAUGCGGCUUCUUCCUCAUUUUGCAGAGCAACCUAAGCGGGCAGAUGUACAAACCGUGUGUUCGAAACCCCUGAGUCCAUGUGUGUGAAAAUGCAGGUUUUCUCUUAGAAAUAAAGUGGUGACUUGUGCUGUA